AUUUUUAGUAGAGAUGGGGUUUUACUGCGUUGGCCAGGCUGGUCUCAAACUCUUGACCACAGGUGGUCCUCCCGCCUAGGGCUUCCAAAGUGCUGGGAUUGCAGGCGUGACCCACCGCGCCUGGCCUGGGUUUCUUUUUUUUUUUCUUGCAGUGGUGUGAUCUCGGCUCACUGCAACCUCUGCCCCCUUGGGUUCAAGCAAUUCUCCUGCCUCACUCAGCCUCCCUGGUAGCUGGGAUUACAGGCAUUCACCACCACGCCCGGUUAAUUUUUGUAUUUUUAGUAGAGAUGGGGUUUUGCCAUGUUGGACAGGCUGGUCUUGAACUCCUGACCUCAAAUGAUCCCCCUGCCUUGGACGCCCAGAAUGCUAGGAUUACAGGCGUGAGCCACUGCGCUCAGACCUGGGUUUCUUUUUAAGCAAAAAAUAAAUUUAAUGAGGACCACAUAAAAAACAUUUGGUAUUGGAUUACGGUUGCAAGGGUCCAUUUAUACAAGGAUUUUCAUCUGCCUCUGUGACUCCUGCGACUGCAAGACCAACCCUUCCUUCUCCUUCUCCUGUUCCUUGUCCUCUUCAGGCUACUCAGUGUGAAGAUGAUGAAGGUGACCACCUUUAUGGUGAUUCACUUCCACUUAGUGAAUAGUAAAUGUAGUUUCUCUUCCUUAUAAUUUUCUUUUUCUUUUUUUUUUGAGACGGAGUCUCGCUCUGUCGCCCAGGUUGGAGUGCAGUGGCACGAUCUCAGCUCACUGCAAGCUCUGCCUCCCAGGUUCAUGCCAUUCUCCUGCCUCAGCCUCCCGAGUAGCUGGGAUCACAGGCGCCCGCCACCACGCCUGGCUAAUUUUUUGUAUUUUUAGUAGAGAAGGGGUUUCACCGUGUUAGCCAGGAUGGUCUCGAUCUCCUGACCUUGUGAUCCAGCCACCUCAGCCUCCCAAAGUGCUGGGAUUACAGGCGUGAGCCACCUGGCCUGGCCUCUUCCUUAUAAUUUUCUUAAUAAUAUUUUGUCUAACUUACUUUAUCACAAAAAUACAGUAACAUGCAAAAUGUAUGUUAAUCAACUAUUUAAGGCAUCAGUCAAUAGACUGCUAAGCUUUUGGGGAAUCAGAAGUUAUAUAUGGAUUUUCUACUGUGUGGGGGGUUGGCGCCCCUAUCUCCUGCAUUAUUCAAUGGUCAACUGUAAUUCUUUUGACUUCGCUUUUUCCUUUCUCAGGCCCUUGAAAAAAAAUUGUUUUUCUUUUUUAGUUUUUAAAUGAUUUUCCAAUGUCGGAUAAAUUAUUUUGGUGAAACGGUAAGGAUGAAGACAUUGUUUCCUACACCUUAAGAAAUAAGCAGCUACAAAAAGCUAGAGUAUUGUACUGAUCUCUGAUUAAGCCAGAUCCUCAAGUGAUGGGGUAUCUUUUUUUAAAAAUUGCUGUGAUUAGUCUUAGGGAGAAAUGAUGACCACCAAAUUCUUCAUAACAUUUAAGGAUUUACCCAGUAAUCCUAUAUUGUGAUUACUUGCAAGAAAGUUAACUAGAAGUAGUGGAUGAUCCUUUUUAGAAUAAUAUUAUUUGCGAUUUAAUAUUUCUCUUUCUACUGUCUUAGUUGUGAUCUUCUAAAAUUUGAUACCAUUCACAUAAAAUAGUGAUUAUUUAUAUCAACACCAUAGGAGUAUUUUCAAGGUAGUUAGUCUUCUCAACCCUCUUUUUUUUUUUUUUUUUUUUUUUUGUGAGACGGAGUCUCUCUCUGUCCCCCAGGCUGGAGUGCAGUGGCGCGAUCUUGGCUCACUGCAAGCUCCACCUCCUGGGUUCACCCCAUUCUUCUGCCUCAGCCUCCUGAGUAGCUGGGACUACAGGUGCCCGCCACCAUGCCCGGCUAAUUUUUUGUAUUUUUUUUUAGUAGAGACGGGGUUUCACCGUGUUAACCAGGAUGGUUUCGAUCUCCUGACCACGUGAUCCACCUGCCUCGGCCUCCCAAAGUGCUGGGAUUACAGGCGUGAGCCACCAUGCCCAGCCUUCUCACCCUCUUUAACCCCAAGGUUGAAAGUGUCAGUGUCCUGGUGAAGACCUAGUUCUUGCCGGAGACAAUUCCACUGCAGAAGCACUUUACUUAAAAGGACUUGCCAGGCUGGACAAUGCCCGUUGACUUGGGGCAGGCCCUAGGCCUGCUGCCAUCGCUGGCGAAGGCCGAGGACUCCCAGUUCUCAGAAUCAGAUGCUGCCCUUCAAGAGGAACUCUCCAGCCCUGAGACCGCACGCCAGCUUUUCAGGCAGUUCCGUUACCAGGUGAUGUCUGGGCCUCAUGAGACCUUGAAGCAACUUCGGAAGCUCUGUUUCCAGUGGCUACAGCCAGAGGUUCACACCAAAGAGCAGAUCCUAGAGAUCCUCAUGUUGGAGCAGUUUCUGACCAUCCUGCCUGGGGAGAUCCAGAUGUGGGUGCGGAAACAGUGUCCAGGAAGUGGAGAAGAGGCAGUGACCCUUGUGGAAAGCUUGAAGGGGGACCCCCAGAGACUGUGGCAAUGGAUCAGUAUCCAGGUUCUAGGACAGGACAUCUUAUCAGAGAAGAUGGAAUCUCCAAGCUGCCAAGUGGGGGAAGUGGAGCCCCAUCUUGAAGUGGUGCCUCAGGAGUUGGGACUUGAGAAUUCAUCCUCAGGGCCUGGGGAGCUUCUGAGCCACAUCGUGAAAGAGGAAUCUGACACAGAAGCAGAACUAGCCCUGGCUGCCUCCCAGCCUGCCCGACUGGAGGAAAGGCUGAUCAGAGACCAGGACCUCGGAGCCUCACUGCUCCCAGCAGCACCUCAGGAACAGUGGAGACAACUGGAUUCCACUCAAAAGGAGCAAUACUGGGAUCUCAUGCUGGAGACCUAUGGGAAAAUGGUCUCAGGAGGCAUUUCCCAUCCCAAAUCUGACCUGACUAAUUCAAUAGAAUUUGGGGAAGAGCUGGCAGGAAUAUACCUUCAUGUCAAUGAGAAGAUCCCAAGACCCACCUGCAUAGGAGAUAGACAAGAGAAUGACAAGGAGAACCUAAAUUUGGAGAAUCACAGGGACCAGGAGCUCCUGCAUGCUUCCUGUCAAGCUUCAGGAGAGGUUCCUUCUCAGGCUUCCUUGAGGGGCUUCUUCACUGAGGAUGAGCCAGGAUGCUUUGGAGAAGGAGAGAAUCUCCCUGAGGCUCUGCAAAACAUUCAGGAUGAGGGAACAGGGGAACAGCUGUCUCCUCAAGAAAGGAUUUCUGAGAAACAACUAGGUCAGCAUUUGCCUAAUCCUCAUUCAGGAGAAAUGUCCACCAUGUGGCUUGAGGAGAAGAGAGAGACCUCCCAGAAGGGGCAGCCAAGAGCCCCCAUGGCCCAGAAGCUCCCCACCUGCAGGGAGUGUGGGAAGACCUUUUAUAGGAAUUCUCAGCUUAUUUUUCACCAAAGAACUCACACCGGAGAGACAUACUUUCAGUGCACCAUCUGCAAAAAAGCCUUUCUGCGGAGUUCAGACUUUGUGAAGCAUCAGAGAACUCACACGGGAGAGAAGCCCUGUAAAUGUGAUUACUGUGGGAAAGGCUUUAGUGACUUCUCAGGAUUGCGCCACCACGAGAAAAUCCACACAGGAGAGAAACCCUAUAAAUGUCCUAUCUGUGAGAAAAGUUUCAUUCAGAGAUCAAACUUUAAUAGACAUCAGAGGGUUCACACUGGAGAGAAACCUUAUAAAUGUUCGCACUGUGGGAAAAGUUUCAGCUGGAGCUCGAGCCUUGACAAACAUCAAAGAUCCCACUUAGGAAAGAAGCCCUUUCAAUAGCCAGUAACCAAACUCUCUUUCCCCAUUUCUAUCUCCCAGCCCAGUCACAAAAAUACUCAGCUCCAUCAAGAGGAAUUGUGUCUAAGAGGAUACCCCUGUUAAUCUCCUUUUUUCUUGGAUUGGAGAGGAGAGAAUCUGGACAUGGCUUUGGACUUGGAGGAUAUCUUGGAUUGGAUUGCACAAUGGCUUAAAUUCUUGAUUCUGCCUCAGGAGAAAGAAUAGUCUUCAUGUUUCCACUCAUCCUUCCUUUGGACCCAUCGGGGAAAAAGUCUAAAUUGGAGAUCCAGUUUUAGAAGUGCUUUCUGGGAAGCAUUUAAUGGGAUUAGCUGUAGUCACUGCUUAUGGGAAGAACCUCAGAUCAGCCCCUUAAAAUGAGUUCUAGAGCAGGUCUUCUGUUCCAGAAGGGGAGAAGCAUAGAGGGCCUGUGAGCUCACGUGUGUUCUUUGUCAUAGGGGUGAAAAACUAACUUCAAGUGUCCCUUGUUUGAAAUAAACUUAGCAGAGUCACUUUCUAUCUUA